GAUGACGACUUUCGGCGCCGUGGCGGAAUGGCGGCUUCCAUCUCUGAGGCGAGCGACGCUAUGGAUCCCACAGGUGAGUGGCGCGGGAUGCGCGCCUGAGACGGUCCGGCGCCCUGGGGGCUUCCCCGAGCCCCUGCGGAGGCCAUCUCCGUUCCUCCGCGAGCCCCAGGACUCGGGCCGGCCAGCCGGCUCUGCCCAGGCAGGGCAGGCUGGGGAGUGGAGGGCCCCGGUUGAGUCUUCUGCCACCCCUCUGGGCCAUGCCUUUGUGCCACCUUCCCGCGCGGCUCGUACACUCUGUCCCGGUCCGUGGUUUGCUAAGAAGGCCAUUUUCAACUCUCCACUGGAGGCUGCUAUGGCGUUCCCUCACCUGCAGCAGCCCAGCUUUCUACUGGCUAGCCUGAAAGCUGACUCUAUAAAUAAGCCCUUUGCACAGCAGUGCCAAGACUUGGUUAAAGUCAUUGAGGACUUUCCAGCAAAGGAGCUGCACACCAUCUUCCCAUGGCUGGUAGAAAGCAUUUUUGGCAGCCUAGAUGGUGUCCUCGUUGGCUGGAACCUCCGCUGCUUACAGGGGCGCGUGAAUCCUGUGGAGUACAGCAUCGUGAUGGAAUUUCUCGACCCUGGUGGCCCAAUGAUGAAGUUGGUUUAUAAGCUUCAAGCUGAAGACUAUAAGUUCGACUUUCCUGUCUCCUACUUGCCUGGUCCUGUGAAGGCGUCCAUCCAGGAGUGCAUCCUCCCUGACAGUCCUCUGUACCACAACAAGGUCCAGUUCACCCCUACUGGGGGCCUUGGUCUGAACUUGGCCCUGAAUCCGUUCGAGUAUUACAUAUUCUUCUUUGCCUUGAGCCUCAUCACUCAGAAGCCACUUCCUGUGUCCCUCCACGUCCGUACUUCAGACUGUGCCUAUUUCAUCCUGGUGGACAGGUACCUGUCAUGGUUCCUGCCCACCGAAGGCAGUGUGCCCCCACCACUCUCCUCCAGCCCAGGGGGGACCAGCCCCUCACCACCUCCCAGGACACCAGCCAUACCCUUUGCUUCCUAUGGCCUCCACCACACUAGCCUCCUAAAGCGACACAUCUCUCAUCAGACGUCUGUGAAUGCAGACCCCGCCUCCCACGAGAUCUGGAGGUCAGAAACUCUGCUCCAGGUUUUUGUUGAAAUGUGGCUUCAUCACUAUUCCUUGGAGAUGUAUCAAAAAAUGCAGUCCCCUCAUGCCAAGCUGGAGGUUCUGCACUACCGACUCAGUGUCUCCAGCGCCCUCUACAGCCCCGCCCAACCCAGCCUCCAGGCCCUCCACGCCUACCAAGAGUCGUUCACGCCUACUGAGGAGCAUGUGUUGGUGGUGCGCCUGCUGCUGAAGCACCUGCACGCCUUUGCCAACAGCCUGAAGCCAGAGCAGGCCUCACCCUCCGCCCACUCCCACGCCACCAGCCCCCUGGAGGAGUUCAAACGGGCUGCUGUCCCGAGGUUCGUCCAGCAGAAACUCUACCUCUUCUUGCAGCAUUGCUUUGGCCACUGGCCCCUGGACGCAUCGUUCAGAGCUGUCCUGGAGAUGUGGCUGAGCUACCUGCAGCCGUGGCGGUACGCGCCUGACAAGCAGGCUCCGGGCAGCGACUCCCAGCCCCGGUGUGUGUCGGAGAAAUGGGCACCCUUUGUCCAGGAGAACCUGCUGAUGUACACCAAGUUGUUUGUGGGCUUUCUGAACCGCGCGCUCCGCACAGACCUGGUCAGCCCCAAGCACGCGCUCAUGGUGUUCCGAGUGGCCAAAGUCUUUGCCCAGCCCAACCUGGCUGAGAUGAUUCAGAAAGGUGAGCAGCUAUUCCUGGAGCCAGAGCUGGUCAUCCCCCACCGCCAGCACCGACUCUUCACGGCCCCCACAUUCACUGGGAGCUUCCUGUCACCCUGGCCACCAGCGGUCACUGAUGCCUCCUUCAAGGUGAAGAGCCACGUCUACAGCCUGGAGGGCCAGGACUGCAAGUACACCCCGAUGUUUGGGCCCGAGGCCCGCACCCUGGUCCUGCGCCUCGCUCAGCUCAUCACACAGGCCAAACACACAGCCAAGUCCAUCUCCGACCAGUGUGCGGAGAGCCCGGCUGGCCACUCCUUCCUCUCAUGGCUGGGCUUUAGCUCCAUGGACACCAAUGGCUCCUACACAGCCAACGACCUGGACGAGAUGGGGCAAGACAGUGUCCGGAAGACAGAUGAAUACCUGGAGAAGGCCCUGGAGUACCUGCGCCAGAUAUUCCGGCUCAGCGAAGCGCAGCUCAGGCAGUUCACACUCGCCUUGGGCACCACCCAGGAUGAGAAUGGAAAAAAGCAACUCCCCGACUGCAUCGUGGGUGAGGACGGACUCAUCCUUACGCCCCUGGGGCGGUACCAGAUCAUCAAUGGGCUGCGAAGGUUUGAAAUUGAGUACCAGGGGGACCCGGAGCUGCAGCCCAUCCGGAGCUAUGAGAUCGCCAGCUUGGUCCGCACACUCUUUAGGCUGUCGUCUGCCAUCAACCACAGAUUUGCAGGACAGAUGGCGGCUCUGUGUUCCCGGGAUGACUUCCUCGGCAGCUUCUGUCGCUACCACCUCACAGAACCUGGGCUGGCCAGCAGGCACCUGCUGAGCCCUGUGGGGCGGAGGCAGGUGGCCGGCCACACCCGCGGCCCCAGGCUCAGCCUGCGCUUCCUGGGCAGUUACCGGACGCUGGUCUCGCUGCUGCUGGCCUUCUUCGUGGCCUCUCUGUUCUGCGUCGGGCCCCUCCCAUGCACGCUGCUGCUCACCCUGGGCUAUGUCCUCUACGCCUCUGCCAUGACACUGCUGACCGAGCGGGGGAAGCUGCACCAGCCCUGAAGGUGUCAGCUGCCUUCAGAGCAGGCUGGAGGGAUUUGCCACACAGCCCCACCCUUGGGCUGAGAGGACCUGGGAAGCCCCUCCAGGAGGGAACACGGUCAUCCUCGGGCUUCUGGAGCGGGGUUCCUGCAGCCGCAGAGGCAUCUGGAGGAAACGCAACCAAGAAAGGAAGGCAGGUGGGCCCCAGCAAAGGAGUAGCUGCCAGGGCUCAACAGCUACGCUCUGUGACAGCGCAGAGCUCAGCGGCGGCCUUUCCCUCCCUCCGCCAAGGACUCACGGCCAAGCCAGCUCUCGGGGCCUUUUUUCCACUGCCCAUUUGGCUACUCUGCUGCACCAAGCUUGGGAGCCAGCCUGCCAACAGCCACCUGGGCCUGGCCUCCCCACUGGCUGGCCUUGAGGUUGGCAGAGUGGGUUGUGGCGCUUCCUCUCUCUGUGUGGGACCAGGACAGUGGCUUAAGUCUCCACUCCAGGAAAGAAUCAAAGUUUCUAGAGUUGUGAGAAAACCAGAGAGUGGCUGUCCUGAUUCUUCACUGUGAGGGGCGUUCUUCAUGUUCUCCCAGCUGUUCCAAGACUGGGCCGUAGAAUUCCAUGUUUCAGGAGCCUAAGACCCUCCCAGAGCCCAGGGGCUUCACCGCAGACCCCAAGCCAUUGAGCACAUCACCCAAAGCAGUGGCCAACAUCGCGGACCCCUGUGCCUUGUCACAGAUGGGUGCUGGUCCUCAGGCGUUGGGGACACUGCUGGGUCGAUGGGGUCGGAUUCUGCCAGUUUCUGCUCUGCAGCCAAAGAUGGUCAGAAGCAUUGUCACUUCAGUAACAUCAAGUGCUCAAAGACAUGGCAACCGUUCAGUGGUACUUAAGUAUUCAAAAUAUACAACUACAGAUUCUCUGACAGAAACCAGCACGGGGUCUUCACCUUCAUUCACCCCACAGGCGACAUGCGAGGGAGAACAGCAUCUCAGUGGUGAUUUCCAAACCAAGCCUUUGUUUUCGGUGUGGGGUUUUGGGGGUUUGCUUUAAUGUUUUUGAAAUUGUAAAUGUUGGGCUUUGUAUUUUGAUGUAAACUGAGCAUAAUGGCAUUUUAGGGCCUGUGACCAAAAAUGAAGCUUGUAACGACCAUGGAUCUGAAUAAACAUGUCCUUGCUUCUGAGUCUUCUGGCACCUGG